AAUGUAAGCGGCGCGAGAGGCGCGGGCGGCGGCGGCGGUGGGAGCGGCGGCUGCAGAAGCAGCAGCAGCAGAAACAGCGGCGGGUACUCUGUGCCCCGCGUCCCGGAGGCAGCCGACUGCGCCACCCCACCCUCGCACGGCCGGGCGGGACCCGCGCCACCAGCCCGGACCUCCGUCGUCCCGCGGCGACCAAAACCCCCGCUGGCCCCACCGCUGUGACUACUCUGGACUCGCCCGCAGAGUUUGCCCGCCGGGGAGGGUGGCCGAUUGGCGGAGCGCACUCCUGCUGUUUUCCCCACCAUCUCGUGGAUGUCGUCCCUCGGGUGGUGAGAGAACUUUGCAGUGGGCUGGAGCGCCCUUUGCGGAGAAGCACACGAAGGUGAAGGAAGGAAAGAAAGAAGACCGAGGAAGAAGGAGCUCGGAAGAAGGGUCCGGAGCGGCCGGUCCGGCCGUGCAGGGCGAGUGCGCCCGAGGCGCGGCGCCCUGAUGCUCCCCGGGCUCGAGGAGCAUUGGGCACUUGCGGGACUGCUCUCGGUGGAGUAGCCCCGUCGGGCCCGGAGGGUUUGUGCAACCGCGGAGAACACCGAGUGCUGGUCGCACGGGGCGUGCCGAGCCGCCUCCCGGCGCGCCCUCCGCACUUUCCCCGCCUCGUCAUCCGUCGCUCCCCGGCCAGGAGCCUCCGCUGCGUCUUCAACCUCGCUCCCCUUUGCGUCCCGGGAGCCUGCGAGCACCCGGCCGAAGGCGCAGCCGAAUCUUGCGGGAGUCGCCCCGAAAGCGUCGGGUUUGUGUGGGGUUAGCGGGGGCCGCCGCGCCACCUGCACCUCGCCCGCCGCCGCCUCGGGGAAAGCCCGAAGAGGAGGCGGACCAGGAGAAGAGCAAAGAAAAGCAGUCCGUCUGGAUUUGUUUGCCCAGGACUGGCGCCGCGCACGCGGAUCGCCGAGGGGAGUGCGGUCGGAGUCACCGCGCCCCCGCCUCCCCGCCCGGGCAGCUGAGGCCGGGGGUUGGAGCGCUGCCCCCGCGCACAGUCCCCGAGCGCCCGACGUCUCCGCGCAGGUUCUUGAAGCAGCUGGGCCUGGGGCGCCCACUAAUGUGGCCCUGAGGGCCGGAGCCCGCACCGACGGGAGCGGGAGCCGGAGCAGCUGCGGGCGCCGAGUGGCCGGUGCGCCCGGCGGAGCGCGCGUGCGUGGCCAGCGCGCUCCCCGCUUCUGCUUGGCUUUCCGGCUUAAUUUUCCUCGGCGGGAUUAAAGUUGGAAAUUGACCGGAGAAUUGAGUUGCCGGGGAACAGAGCCCCGGCCGCCGCCAGAGCGAUGUUCCCGCAGAGCCGGCACCCGACGCCGCACCAGGCUGCAGGCCAGCCCUUCAAGUUCACUAUCCCGGAGUCCCUGGACCGGAUUAAAGAGGAAUUCCAGUUCCUGCAGGCGCAGUAUCACAGCCUUAAAUUGGAAUGUGAGAAACUGGCAAGUGAAAAGACAGAAAUGCAGAGGCACUAUGUGAUGUAUUAUGAAAUGUCAUAUGGAUUAAACAUUGAAAUGCACAAACAGACUGAAAUCGCCAAGAGAUUGAAUACGAUUUGUGCACAAGUCAUCCCAUUUCUGUCUCAGGAACAUCAACAACAGGUGGCCCAGGCUGUUGAACGUGCCAAACAGGUGACCAUGGCAGAAUUGAAUGCCAUCAUCGGGGUACGUGGCCUACCAGGUCUACCUCCUACACAGCAGCAGUUGCAAGCUCAGCAUCUUUCUCAUGGCCACGGACCCCCAGUUCCCCUUACGCCUCACCCUUCGGGACUUCAGCCUCCUGGAAUCCCGCCCCUCGGGGGCAGUGCCGGCCUUCUUGCGCUGUCUAGUGCUCUGAGUGGGCAGUCUCACUUGGCAAUAAAAGAUGACAAGAAGCACCACGAUGCAGAGCACCACAGAGACAGAGAGCCGGGCACAAGUAAUUCCCUCCUGGUCCCAGACAGUCUAAGAGGCACAGAUAAACGCAGAAAUGGACCUGAAUUUUCCAAUGACAUCAAGAAAAGGAAGGUGGAUGAUAAGGACUCCAGCCACUAUGACAGUGAUGGUGACAAAAGCGAUGACAACUUAGUUGUGGAUGUGUCUAAUGAGGACCCUUCUUCUCCGCGAGCAAGCCCUGCCCACUCGCCCCGGGAAAAUGGAAUCGACAAAAAUCGCCUGCUAAAGAAGGAUGCUUCUAGCAGUCCAGCUUCCACGGCCUCCUCGGCAAGUUCCACUUCUUUGAAAUCCAAAGAAAUGAGCUUGCAUGAAAAAGCCAGCACGCCUGUUCUGAAAUCCAGCACACCAACGCCUCGGAGCGACAUGCCAACGCCGGGCACCAGCGCCACUCCAGGCCUCCGUCCAGGUCUCGGCAAGCCUCCAGCCAUAGACCCCCUCGUUAACCAAGCGGGAUUGGAUUUUCAUUUGGAAUUGGUACCAGGGAAUGGAAAGUUCGGACUGAAAGAGAAAUCUUGGAUUUUAUCGAGAAAAUCUUCUUUUGAGAUUAAGUCAGCAGCUGGCUUGAGGACACCCCUGGCAGUGCCCGGCCCAUAUCCUGCUCCUUUUGGGAUGGUCCCCCACGCUGGCAUGAACGGCGAGCUGACCAGCCCAGGCGCUGCCUACGCCAGUUUACACAACAUGUCGCCCCAGAUGAGCGCCGCAGCCGCCGCGGCCGCCGUGGUGGCCUACGGGCGCUCCCCCAUGGUGGGGUUUGAUCCUCCCCCUCACAUGAGAGUACCUACCAUUCCUCCAAACCUGGCAGGAAUCCCUGGGGGGAAACCUGCAUACUCCUUCCACGUUACUGCAGACGGUCAGAUGCAGCCUGUCCCUUUUCCCCCCGACGCCCUCAUCGGACCCGGAAUCCCCCGGCAUGCUCGCCAGAUCAACACCCUCAACCACGGGGAGGUGGUGUGCGCUGUGACCAUCAGCAACCCCACGAGACACGUGUACACAGGCGGGAAGGGCUGCGUCAAGGUCUGGGACAUCAGCCACCCUGGCAAUAAGAGCCCUGUCUCCCAGCUCGACUGUCUGAACAGAGACAAUUAUAUCCGUUCCUGUAAAUUGCUACCCGAUGGCUGCACUCUCAUAGUGGGAGGGGAAGCCAGUACUUUGUCCAUUUGGGACCUGGCGGCUCCAACCCCGCGCAUCAAGGCGGAGCUGACGUCCUCGGCCCCCGCCUGCUACGCCCUGGCCAUCAGCCCCGAUUCCAAGGUCUGCUUCUCAUGCUGCAGCGACGGCAACAUCGCUGUGUGGGAUCUGCACAACCAGACACUAGUGAGGCAAUUCCAGGGCCACACAGACGGAGCCAGCUGUAUUGACAUUUCUAAUGAUGGCACCAAGCUCUGGACGGGUGGUUUGGACAACACAGUCAGGUCCUGGGACCUGCGCGAGGGGCGGCAGCUGCAGCAGCACGACUUCACCUCCCAGAUCUUCUCCCUGGGGUACUGCCCCACCGGGGAGUGGCUGGCAGUGGGCAUGGAGAGCAGCAAUGUGGAGGUGCUGCACGUGAACAAGCCUGACAAGUACCAGCUGCACCUGCAUGAGAGCUGCGUGCUGUCCCUGAAAUUUGCUUACUGUGGUAAAUGGUUUGUGAGUACUGGAAAAGAUAACCUCCUCAAUGCUUGGCGGACCCCCUAUGGAGCCAGCAUAUUCCAGUCCAAAGAGUCCUCGUCAGUGCUUAGCUGUGACAUCUCUGUGGAUGAUAAGUACAUAGUCACUGGCUCGGGGGACAAGAAGGCUACAGUCUAUGAAGUCAUCUACUGAAAACAUUAUGUGGUUUAACGUUUAUAGUUGAAUUGGGCCAAAAUGUUUCGAAUUUAUAGAAAUAGAAAAGUUGUAACUUUAAAAGAGAAAAAAAAUUACAAACACCUGUUUCCAAACCUUGACAGAAAACUACUUUGAGUCUACAAAGAGGAGGCGACAAGUCCAUCAGCAGAAAGUCACCUGUCUACAUAGACCAAAUGGAGCACCAAGGCCAAGCGGACAGAGGGGCCAUGGGUUGUAGGAUUGAGGAACGGAAUCUGCCGACUCACAUGACAGCCCAUUCUUUCUUUCUGGGUGAUCUGGGGAUCACGCCUUGCCCAAGUGUGAGAUUACCUUUCUGUUCCUUGCAGUUCACCUCACUUUCCGUCCUUUGUAGAGCAGUGGUGUCUCCAAUGAACUUGUUUCCUGGUUUUGCAUCUUGUGAAAUGUUUUUUUGUAUUUUUGUUGAAGGUUAAACAUUUGUAUAAAUUGUAAAUAUAUUUGGUUUAUUACAGUAAAGGCUUUAGUACCAAUAA